GUCUCUCGCUGCAGUCAGAGCUCCAGGUCUGGUUCUUCUCCUAAAGGCCCAGGCUGUGUGGCCCCGUGUCCUGCAGGUAUUGGGAGAUCCACAGCUAAGACACCGGGACCUCCUGGAAGCCAAAAAUGGGACCAUUGCAAUUUAGAGAUGUGGCCAUAGAAUUCUCUCUGGAGGAGUGGCAUUGCCUGGACACUGCACAGCGGAAUUUAUAUAGGAAUGUGAUGUUAGAGAACUACAGUAACCUGGUCUUCCUUGGUAUUACUGUUUCUAAGCCAGACCUGAUCACCUGUCUGGAGCAAGGAAGAAAACCUUUGACCAUGAAGAGAAAUGAGAUGAUAGCCAAACCCUCAGUAAUGUGUUCUCAUUUUGCCCAAGACCUUUGGCCAGAGCAGAGCAUGAAAGAUUCUUUCCAAAAAGUGGUACUGAGAAGAUAUGAAAAAUGUGAACAUGACAAUUUACAGUUAAAAAAAGGAUGUAUAAGUGUGGAUGAGUGUAAGGUGCACAAAGAAGGUUAUAAUGAACUUAACCAAUGUUUGACAACUACCCCAAGAAAAAUAUGUCAAUGUGAUAAAUAUGUGAAAGUCCUUCAUCAAUUUCCAAAUUCAAACGGACAAAAGAGAGGACAUACUGGGAAAAAACCUUUCAAAUAUAUAGAAUGUGGCAAAGCUUUUAAGCAGUUCUCAACUCUUACUACACAUAAGAAAAUUCAUACUGGAGGGAAACCCUACAAAUGUGAAGAAUGUGGCAAAGCCUUUAACCACUCUUGUAGCCUUACUAGACAUAAGAAAAUUCAUACUGGAGAGAAACCCUACAAAUGUGAAGAAUGUGGCAAAGCCUUUAAGCACUCCUCCACUCUUACUACACAUAAGAGAAAUCAUACUGGAGAGAAACCCUACAAGUGUGAUAAAUGUGGCAAAGCCUUUAUGUCAUCCUCAACCCUUAGUAAACAUGAGAUAAUUCAUACGGAAAAGAAACCCUACAAAUGUGAAGAAUGUGGCAAAGCCUUCAACCGGUCCUCAACCCUUACUACACAUAAGAUAAUUCAUACUGGAGAAAAACCCUACAAAUGUGAAGAAUGUGACAAAGCCUUUAAGUACUCCUAUACCCUUACUACACAUAAAAGAAUUCAUACUGAAGACAAACCCUACAAAUGUGAAGAAUGUGGCAAAGCCUUUAAGUACUCCUCUACCCUUACUACACAUAAGAGAAUUCAUACUGGAGAGAAACCCUACAAAUGUGAAGAAUGUGGCAAAGCCUUCAAGCGGUCUUCAGACCUUACUACGCAUAAGAUAAUUCAUACUGGAGAGAAACCCUACAAAUGUGAAGAAUGUGGCAAAGCUUUUAAGUACUCCUCUAACCUUACUACACAUAAGAAAAUUCAUACUGGAGAGAGACCCUACAAAUGUGAAGAAUGUGGCAAAGCCUUCAACCAGUCCUCAAUCCUUACUACACAUAGGAGAAUUCAUACUGGAGAGAAAUUCUACAAAUGUGAAGAAUGUGGCAAAGCUUUUAAGUGCUCCUCUAACCUUACUACACAUAAGAAAAUUCAUACUGGAGAGAGACCCUACAAAUGUGAAGAAUGUGGCAAAGCCUUCAACCAGUCCUCAAUCCUUACUACACAUGAGAGAAUCAUACUGGAGAGAAAUUCUACAAAUGUGAAGAAUGUGGCAAAGCCUUCAAGCGGUCCUCACACCUUACUACACAUAAGAUAAUUCAUACUGGAGAGAAAUUCUACAAAUGUGAAGAAUGUGACAAAGCUUUUAAGCAUUUCUCUAACCUUACUACACAUAAGAAAAUUCAUACUGGAAAAAAACCCUACAGAUGUGAAGAAUGUGGCAAAGCCUUUAAGCACUCCUCUAAACUUACUACACAUAAGAGAUUUCAUACUGGAGAGAAACCCUACAGAUGUGAAUAAUGUGGUAAAGCUUUUCACCUAUCCUCACACCUUACUGCACAUAAGAUAAUUCAUACUGGAGAGAAACCAUGUGAAUGUGAUGAAUGGGGAAAAUCUUUUAACCAGCCCUCAAUUUCUAACUAAGAAUUGAUAUGAAAUAUAAACUCUACAAAUAUAAAGAAUGUGACAGAUUUUUUAAGGAACUUCUCAACCUUUAUUACACAUAAUUCAUACUGGAAAGAAACCCUACAAGUGUGAAGAAUGUGGCAAAGCAUAUAACAAGUUCUGUCUUUUUUUUUUUUUUUUUGAGAUGGAGUUUCAACUCUUGUCACCCAGUCUGGUGUGCAAUAGCACAGUCUCGGCUCACUGCAACCUCCGCCUUCUGGGUUCAAUCCAUUCUCCUGCCUCAACCUCCCAAGUAAGGGGGAUUACAGGUGCCCACCCCCAUGCCCAGCUAACUUUUGUAUUUUUAGUAGAGACAAGGUUACACCAUGUUUGUCAGGCUGGUAUCCAACCCCUGACCUCACAUGAUCCACCCACCUCAGCCUCCUAAAGUGUUGCAAUUACAGGCAUGAGCCACCAUGCCUGGCCACAAGUUCUUACUAUUAAGAGACAUGGUGAUAAUUCAUUCUGAAGAGGAACUCUACAAACCUGAAAGAUGUGACAGUGCUUUUUUCAACACUUCCAUCCUUUCUAUACAUAAAAAAUUUAUACUAGUGUGAAACCCUAGAAAUAUAUAAAAUGUGAAACAGCCUUUAUAUGGUUGCCACAUUUGAUAGUAAGAUAAUUCAUACUGGCAAAAUUCCUACAAGCAUGAAGAAUGUGGCAAAACCUUUAAUCAAUGUGUACAUCUUAUUUUGCAGGAAAGCUAUUAUCCUUGAGAAAAAUUGUACAAAUAUAAAGAAUAUGGAAAACCCAUUAAUGCCUACUCACAUCUUACUCAACAUAAGAAGGUUCAUAGUUAAUGAAAGCAUUAAAAGUGCAAUUACUGUCAAAAAAUCUUUCAGAAAAUAUAAGCCUUUAAAGUGAAGAAGAGUAUUUAUUCUGAAGACAACCAUUACAAAUAUACAGGAGGUUUAUUACACACAUUUUGUACUAGAGGAAAAUCCUGAAGCAGUUGCUCAAGCUUUGCUCAACAUCAGAGAACUUAUAUUGGAGAAGGGUCCUGCAAAUGUAAUGAAUUUGGAAACACUUUAAAAAAAAAAAACUACAGCUUAGAAAACAGCAGAGUUUAUACUAAAAUAUAUUUUUGCAGAUGCAGUAAACAUGAAAAAAUAUUUAAUUCAAAAUUAAUUGUAUGUAAAUAUCAGAAUUUACAGAAUAACUAAGGCACUGACACUUCAGACAUUACAUUAAAUAAGAGUGUUGAGUAUAUAAAUGAAUUCACAACUAAAGUUGUUAAAUUUGUAUAUAAGUUUGUAUAAAUUAGUAUAUAACUUUAAAAGGAGAUUUUUUGAAGCUUUGUAUUUACAUUGAAAGUAUAUUUGUUUCCUUGAAAACAAUUUUUUUGAAAAGUGAAUGAUGUAAUACAGCUUUCAAAUUAUGCUGUUACUUUAUUAUAUUCACGUGAAAGUAUGUGAUCAAUUGUUGCUGCAUCAGAGAUAUUAGAGAUUCUUUAUGAGUUGGGCAUUCUUUAUGACCUUUUCUAUAAAACAGUAAGGACAUUAAAAUGUAAGAUGCAUGACGAAAAUAUAAGUGGAGAGGCUCAUUGUAGUUAACCUAUAUUAAGUAAUGUUUAAGGUAGGUGUUCAGAGUAAUACUUUUCUACAUUAUACUGAGAGAAAGAAAUUAUAAAUUAAAGUAUAUCAAUUAUUUUACUAAUUUUACUGUUACGUAAUAAAAUGCAAUAUAUUUAAAAAUUGUUAGAUGAUGUGUGAACUUAACUUAUAUUUUAUUUACUUACUUAACUUUUCUUUUGAGAUGGAGUCUUGCUCUGUCACCCAGGCUGGAGGGCAGCAGUGCAGUCUCAGCACAAUGACUGCAACCUCCACCUCCCAAGUUCAAGAAAUUCUCCUGCCUCAGCCUCCCGAGUAGUGGGGACUACAGGUGCGUGACACCACGCCUGGCUAAUUUUUAUAUUUUUAAUAGACAUGGGGUUUCCCCAUAUUGGUCAGGCUAGUCUCAAACUCCUGAGCUCAAGCGAUCCACCCACCUCAGGCUCUCAAAGUGUUGGGAUUAUAGGUGUGAGCCAAUAUGUCCAGCCUAAUUUUAUUUUAUUUUUUACCAUCUUAAAACUAUUGUGCAUUUAAUGAAGCAUUAUUAUGCCACUAACUUUAACCUAUCCGGCCUUACUCAAAUGGUGUAAGCAAAAGAUGGAAGAAGUAUACUAUUUGGUAUGUAGUGGAAUGUCAUCACUAGUAAUCACUUUGCCAGUAAACUGCAAAUGAAGAAUAUUGUUCCCGUUAGUUAAAUUUUUAAUCUUUUUUCUUAAUUUAUUAUUACUAUCUGUGAGUAUAUAGUAUGUGUAUAUAUGUCUUAUAGAGAAUAUUUUGAUUCAGGCAUACAAUAUGUAGUAAUUACAUUAGGGUAAAUAAGGUAUCUGUCACCUCUAGCAUUUAUCCUUUCUAAUCCAAACAGUGUAAUUAUACACUUUUAGUUACUUUUAAAUGUCCAAUUAAAUUGUAAUUGACUACAGGGUGAUUUUUAUGGUCAUAAUAAAAAUUAUACAGAAAUAUAAAUAGAAUAUGGGCUGGACGCAGUGGCUCAUGCCUGUAAUCCCAGCACUUUGGUAGGCGACGUCGGGCAGAUCAUGAGGUCAGGAGUUCAAGACCAGCCUGACCAACAUUGUGAAACUCUCUACUAAAACAACAAAAAUUAGUUGGGCAUGGUGGUGCACCCGUAUUCCUAGCUACUCGGGAAGCUGAGGCAGGAGAAUGGCUUGAACCUGGGAGGUGGAGGUUUCAGUGAGCUGAGAUAGCACCACUGCACUCCAGCCUGGGUGACAGACGGACACUCCAUCUCAAAAAGAAAGAAAAAAGCCAGGACAGUGGCUUACACCUGUAAUCCCAGCACUUUGGGAGGCCCAGGCAGGUGGAUCAUGAGGUCAGGAGAUCAAGACCAUCCUGGCUAACACGUUGAAACCCUGUCUCUACUAAAAAUAAAUUAGCUGGGCGUGGUGGUGGGCGCCUGUAGUCCCAGCUACUCCAGAGGCUGAGGCGGGAGAAUGGUGUAACCCAGGAGGCAGAGGUUGCAGUGAGCCGAGAUCGUGCCACUGCACUCCAGCCUGGGCAACAGAGCAAGACUCCGUCACAAAAAAAAAAAGAAAAAAUACGGCCAUGUGCAGUGCCUCAUGCCUAUUAUCCCAGCAAUUUCGGAGGCUGAGGCAGGUGUGUUGCUUGAGCUCAGGAGUUCAAGACCAGCCUCGCCAAUGUGGUGAAACCCUGUCUCUACUAAAAAUAGAAAAAUUAGCCAGUCAUGGUGGCGCACACCUGGAGGCUGAGGUAGGAGAAUCACUUGAACUUGGGAGGUGGAGAUUGCAGUGAGCCAAGAUUGUGCUGCUGCACUCCAGCCUGGGUGACAGAGUGAUGAGACUCCUCAAAGGAAAAAAAAUUACAUUUCUGAGUCCUGAAAAAUUAUUAAUAAAUAUUUGUUAUAUAGUUUCUUUGAACAUGUGGUCACUCUGCCUGCAAACGUAAAGACUUUUAAUUUUCAUAGAGUGAAAUAUACACAUAUUCCUCUGAAGAUAAACCUUAGGUGUAAGAAAAUUAUGAAAUGAGUGUUUGGUAAAUAUGCAUUUGUACAUAUUUUCAGAAGAAAACGCAAUUAUUGGAACAAAAUAAGUUUUUAGGUGAUUAAUGGAAAACUAAACACCUUGAAUAUGCUGAAAGCAAAUGUAUACUUUCUGCUUUGUAUGGAAUUUAUUAAUAUAAAAUUUUAUGGCUUAUGGCUCGGAUUCUCCCCAGAAUCCGUGUAUUAAAGCACAGGCAACUUUGUCUCCAGAAAUAACACUCUUGAGUACAACAAUAAAAGCCCUCUUCAAACACACUCAAAAAAUUAUUUUUAACGCUUAUUUUAAUAAAAAUUUAACCAAAAUUGAAUAAUUGGAUACAUUUUUAUUGUUCUAUGUGUGUGUGAAUGUAUAAAAUGACACAUAAAGGAAUAAUAAUUUAAGCCAGAAAAAAAGAUGUUAGUUAAUAUUUGUAAUGAAUAAAACUGGAAAGUAGUUAUUA